AUGAUCAAUGUCCCCCACCCGACGGCCGCCGCGGCGGCGGCGGCGGCGCGGCCCCGGCCGGGGAGCGGAGUCCGCGGUGGAGGCGCGGGAGGGGCCGGGCCCCUCCCGACGGGACUCCCCCGCGGGCCCACCACCGCCCCCGACCCACGGGCGGACGGGCGAUCCCCCCAAGGGGUCUUUAAACCUCCGCGCCGGAACGCGCUAGGUACCUGGACGGCGGGGGGGCGGACGAGGAGGCGGGGGAGGGGACCGGCGUCCGGCCCCCGACCCUCGAGACGCCCUAGCGGGAAGGCCGGGGAGAGCGAGCGGGGCCGUGCCCGGCGGCGCGGAGCGGCGCGGCGGAGGCGACGGGAAUCCGGCCGGCCCCGAAGACGGGGAGCCGGCGCGGCGGGGCCGGACGACGGGCCCCGGCGGGGAGGAGGGCACCGAGACCCCCCAGACCCGCCGCGACGCCGCCGAGAACCGCCCCCGCGCCCGCCGACACCCACGUCGUCGGGGCCGCGGCCGGGGACCGCUCCCCGCCGCCCGCCGGCCCCACGACACGCGCACACCAACGACACGCCCUUCUUUCUCUCUCUCUCUCUCUCUCUCCCCCCCGUCUCCCUCCCGAGUUCUCCGGCUCUCGCGGCCGGCGGGGCCGGGCGGCGAACGAACGAGCGAGCGAACGAACGGGCACGCGGGCCCCGCCCGCGCACGCGCCGCGUCGCGGUGGGGGGGCGGGUGUGCGGAGGGAAGCGCGCGGCGGCGGCGGCGCCGCCGCGGGCCUCGCCCUCCGGGCUCCGUUAAUGAUCCUUCCGCAGGUUCACCUACGGAAACCUUGUUACGACUUUUACUUCCUCUAGAUAGUCAAGUUCGACCGUCUUCUCAGCGCUCCGCCAGGGCCGUGGGCCGACCCCGGCGGGGCCGAUCCGAGGGCCUCACUAAACCAUCCAAUCGGUAGUAGCGACGGGCGGUGUGUACAAAGGGCAGGGACUUAAUCAACGCAAGCUUAUGACCCGCACUUACUGGGAAUUCCUCGUUCAUGGGGAAUAAUUGCAAUCCCCGAUCCCCAUCACGAAUGGGGUUCAACGGGUUACCCGCGCCUGCCGGCGUAGGGUAGGCACACGCUGAGCCAGUCAGUGUAGCGCGCGUGCAGCCCCGGACAUCUAAGGGCAUCACAGACCUGUUAUUGCUCAAUCUCGGGUGGCUGAACGCCACUUGUCCCUCUAAGAAGUUGGGGGACGCCGACCGCUCGGGGGUCGCGUAACUAGUUAGCAUGCCAGAGUCUCGUUCGUUAUCGGAAUUAACCAGACAAAUCGCUCCACCAACUAAGAACGGCCAUGCACCACCACCCACGGAAUCGAGAAAGAGCUAUCAAUCUGUCAAUCCUGUCCGUGUCCGGGCCGGGUGAGGUUUCCCGUGUUGAGUCAAAUUAAGCCGCAGGCUCCACUCCUGGUGGUGCCCUUCCGUCAAUUCCUUUAAGUUUCAGCUUUGCAACCAUACUCCCCCCGGAACCCAAAGACUUUGGUUUCCCGGAAGCUGCCCGGCGGGUCAUGGGAAUAACGCCGCCGCAUCGCCGGUCGGCAUCGUUUAUGGUCGGAACUACGACGGUAUCUGAUCGUCUUCGAACCUCCGACUUUCGUUCUUGAUUAAUGAAAACAUUCUUGGCAAAUGCUUUCGCUCUGGUCCGUCUUGCGCCGGUCCAAGAAUUUCACCUCUAGCGGCGCAAUACGAAUGCCCCCGGCCGUCCCUCUUAAUCAUGGCCUCAGUUCCGAAAACCAACAAAAUAGAACCGCGGUCCUAUUCCAUUAUUCCUAGCUGCGGUAUCCAGGCGGCUCGGGCCUGCUUUGAACACUCUAAUUUUUUCAAAGUAAACGCUUCGGGCCCCGCGGGACACUCAGCUAAGAGCAUCGAGGGGGCGCCGAGAGGCAAGGGGCGGGGACGGGCGGUGGCUCGCCUCGCGGCGGACCGCCCGCCCGCUCCCAAGAUCCAACUACGAGCUUUUUAACUGCAGCAACUUUAAUAUACGCUAUUGGAGCUGGAAUUACCGCGGCUGCUGGCACCAGACUUGCCCUCCAAUGGAUCCUCGUUAAAGGAUUUAAAGUGGA